AAUCGCUAGCAAACUCCCUGCCUAGCAAGGCCCAGCCUGGGGCAGAAAUGGCUGCAAGUGGCCGAGGUCUCUGCAAGGCUGUGGCCGCCUCUCCCUUCCCGGCGUGGAGACGAGAUAACACGGAAGCCAGGGGAGGUCUGAAGCCUGAGUAUGAUGCGGUGGUGAUAGGAGCAGUUGCUAAACAUACCAUAAAGCCUGGUUUAAAGGCAUCUUGGGCCUCAGUGAGGAACAGAACGGCAUCUUCUGAGACAAGGGUUACCUCUGAGUCCCUGAAGGCACACUGGCACCUGGCCGCCACCUUGAAGAUGAAUCUCAUUUAGUCAUUUGACUAAAUGUGCCUGAGAGUGACUGAGGGGGCUUGUUAAAAUGGAGAUUCCUGGCCCCAUACCUGGUGACGAGCAUUCUGAGGGCGGGAGGUGUCUCCCAGAGGUCAGCACAUCCACCCAACCAACACUGCCUGAUGCAGGCAGCUGCAGAGCCCACGCCCAGAGCAGCUCCUCAAGGGCCCAGGCGCCUGCUAUGGGGCCCCUGAGGCAGGUCUGGGGAUUAGCAGAGCCCGCAGCUGAAGUCCUCUUCAAGGGAACAGAGGUGUCACCAGAAGCCAAGGAGGGCUCAGCCAGGACUUGAGGGUGGUCACUGGGAGGGGGUCUUGUGCUUUGGAUCCUUGACCUUACUCAUUUGAGGUCUGCCAUGAUUGAACUGGACCCAGUUGCCUGGAAGACUAUGAGUUUUCCAAGAUCGAUCAUCAGCACCAAUUAAAAGACAAAUAGCUCCCAUUUAUCUCAUCCUUGCCACACUGCAGGGUCCCUGGCACCCUCUGUUCCCCAUGUGAAGAAACUCAAGGCUCAGGGCAGCUGAUGACUCUCUGAGGUCAUGCCCUGGCAAAUAGCAGAGGCUGGGCUGAGCCCAGGACUGUCUGCCUUUAGUUUGCUGCAUGUCUUUGAGAGACAGAUUCCAUCUGUUCAUGAGUCCCACUGGCGGAUUGUUUAAACUUUCUUAUGAACAUUUUCAAAAGCCCAUACAAAUAAAGAGUAUGUCAACCAGCACUUUUUAAGAUGAACUGUAACCAACUAGCUUCUCACAUGCUUCUCAUAUGGUAAGAGUUAAUUUUAGCUCAUGAAACUUUUGGUUCUGUGAAACACCUGCUGAACAGACUCCUGGGAAGGGGGUCUGUGGGAGUCGACAUUUAUACAACCUUCCAGGUGAUUCUGAGCUUAUCAGAGCUGGAGAGGCACUUGCUACCCAGGGGCUUGGUGUGGAACGUGAGAUGCCAAAGCCAAAUUCAGGCCUCUCAGCUCAAGGCACCCUGAAGCACAGCUAGUCACUCCAGCACAUGUUGAAGCUGUGCAUGUUUACUUCAUGUUGAACUGUUCAUGUUUUAUUUUUGGAACACUGGGGAUUGGCAAAAAAAAAAAAAACCCAUGUGAAUAAAGCCUUCUAGGGCACCACUGUGCCGAUUGUGAACCACACGUGGACAAAACAAGCCGCGCUUGAUAGCAACUACCUACAUGACCAGCACUCCCCUGGAUGCUGAUGCUGCCAUGCGAGACGGGACGUUGGCGCAGCAGCAUGCCAGCCACCCAUUGCUUCUCCUGCUUGCCAACUCAACCGUGCUGCUCCCUCAGACACCAUCACUUGCGCCUCCCAAGCAAUGGAAGCCCUGGCGAUGCUCUCAUGAGCCCCUCACUCCAGCAGAGCCCCUGACCAAGCCAGGGGAGCAGGACUUUUCCAGCCAAGGACACAACGGACUGGUGGCUGCAGCGUACCUGCAGAGACUGGGGGUGAACACCGCCGUCUUCGAGAGGCGCCAUGUGAUCGGGGGUGCAGCUGUCACUGAGGAGAUCAUCCCAGGGUUUAAGUUCUCCCGCGCGUCCUACCUGCUCAGCCUGCUGAGGCCGCAGAUUUACACUGAUCUGGAGCUGAAGAAACAUGGGCUGAGGCUUCAUCUUCGAAACCCCUACUCCUUCACCCCCAUGCUGGAAGAGGGUGCAGGCAGCAAGGUGCCCAGGUGCCUUCUGCUGGGCACAGACAUGGCAGAAAACCAGAAGCAGAUCGCCCAGUUCUCCCAGAAGGAUGCCCAGGUCUUUCCCAAAUAUGAGGAGUUCAUGCAUCGCUUGGCAUUAGCCAUUGACCCUCUGCUGGAUGCGGCCCCCGUGGACAUGGCGGCCUUCCAGCAUGGCUCCUUGCUGCAAAGGAUGAGGUCGCUCUCCACCCUCAAGCCCCUGCUGAAGGCAGGCCGCAUCCUGGGAGCCCAGCUUCCCCGAUAUUAUGAGGUCCUCACAGCUCCCAUUACCAAGGUGCUGGAUCAGUGGUUCGAGUCUGAGCCUUUAAAAGCCACUCUAGCCACAGAUGCAGUGAUUGGAGCCAUGACAAGUCCCCACACUCCGGGGAGUGGGUAUGUGCUGCUGCACCAUGUGAUGGGGGGCCUGGAGGGAAUGCAGGGGGCCUGGGGCUACGUCCAGGGGGGCAUGGGUGCCCUCUCUGAUGCGAUCGCAAGCUCAGCCACCACACAUGGAGCAAGCAUCUUCACUGAAAAGACAGUGGCGAAGGUGCAGGUGAACAGUGAAGGCUGUGUUCAAGGAGUUGUGCUGGAAGAUGGCACAGAGGUGAGAAGCAAAAUGGUGCUGUCCAACACAUCACCGCAGAUCACCUUCCUGAAGCUGACGCCACAGGAGUGGCUUCCUGAGGAGUUCCUGGAGAGAAUCUCUCAGCUGGACACCCGGUCGCCUGUCACCAAGAUCAAUGUGGCCGUAGACAGGCUGCCCAGCUUCCUGGCGGCCCCCAAUGCUCCCAGGGGCCAGCCGCUGCCCCAUCACCAAUGCUCCAUCCACCUGAACUGUGAAGACACCCUCCUCCUUCAUCAGGCCUUUGAAGAUGCCAUGGAUGGCCUGCCUUCCCACAGGCUUGGUUCAGUGAGUGGGCACAGAUCAGCAAGCAAAGCCAAGAAAGUCUCAGGUCGUUGACUCUCUAUCCAUGAGAGGAAGACAAUCAACAAGUAAGCACUGAUGAUGAGCACUGUGGAGAAAAAUAGGCAGGGAAGGGGAGGAAAGGCUUCUCUAAUAACGUGGCACUUGAGCGGAGACCGGAAGGAAGUGAGAAUACAGAUCUUAUGGGUAUCUGGGGAAAAAACGUCCAGACAGAGGGAAGGUCAGGUGCAAAGGCCCUGGGGCAGGAGUGUGCUGCUGUAUAGGAGGCACAGGGACGAGGCCAGAGUGGCUGGAGAGAGAGCACCUGGGAAUGAAGGGUCUCGGAUGGUGCUGGGUCUUGUCAAGUGCCCUGGCUCUUACUCCAGGAAAGUUUGUGCAGAGCCUGCCUUAUGCUUUAAAAAGACCAACCUGGACACUGUAUGCAGAAAAAGUUAAGGCAUCUGUUGCAAUGGGUUACUGUUGCAGAAUCCAAGGGAGAGAGGACAGUGGCUUGGACAAGGGUGGGGGCAGGGGAAGUGAUGAGAAGUGUUGGAAGACUGGGUAUGUUUUGAAGGUGAAGCCAACAGGACUUUCUGUUGGAUAGGGAGUGGGAUGUGGGUCAAAAAAAGGAGCGACUGUGAAAUGAUGCCUCCAUUUACUGAAAAGAGGAAGAGGCGGUGGGGGUGGAGCAGAUUUUAGAGGCUAAUCAGGCAUUGGGGUUUGAACAGGGGAUGUUUGAGAUCCCUGGUGGACAUCCGAGUUCAGCGAGAACAUUGCAGCUGAGGGACGCAGGGAGAAGGGGCAUUUCCCGUGGCCUUGAAGGAGACUCAUAUUUGGAGAUCAGAGGGAGAACAUGCUCCAGGUAGAAAAGGUGUGGCAGGCAAAGGUGGUGGGGUGGGAAGCAGGUCACAGCUCUGCUGGGGCUCGGGGCAGCCCUAGCAGCUCUGUCUUCCAUUGGUCUGCUCUGGAAAAGACAGUCAGGCCACUAAAGCCUGGCUGAAAUCUGGCUGCUUGGGCGCCUGCUGUCUUAGGCCUGGCCCCUUUCCACACUCCCACUGUCUGUGUGGACCUUCGAGACAUUUGCGUUUGGGAGCUGUGGUUAGAGCACAGCGUGUGAUGAAGGCAGGCAAGGACAGGCCAUGCAUUCGGGGGUCUGGGGUCAGGCGAGCUCCUCACAGGUGCUCUGGACCACGCUAGCAGCCGCUAAGCCCGUGCAGGUGGACAACCACUGUGGCUGUAGAGCGACAAUCGCCCAGAAUUGGUGUCAUCUCAGGGCCUCCACUGUGUCCCAAGUCAUCUCGGAUGCCCUACCCUCCGCACUGCUGCUCUUUAGACCUGCCGUCUCCUCCCUGCCC